AUCCCCGCACCAAGCGCUUAACCUCAUUGGGGUGGAGGAGAAGGCGGCGGCUCUCUGGUCCGCAGCGGCAACAGUAACGAAAAACAGGGCUAAUGGACUGCUGAAUUAUGAAGUAUUUCAGACCCAGUAGUAGAACAUCACUCUGCCACUCACUCCUUUAUCUCCUACUAGUUAUUUAAAUUGGACUUUUAAUAUCCUACCAGCUGCUCUUCAGACACACAUGGUGCAUUGUUGCCAUUCCCCAGAUUGCAUCUUUGAAACACAGGCUCUUAGUAACCUUCAGCGAACAAAGAGGCAACCUCCCAGAUACGUCUGCUGGGAGGGAGUCAUCGUGACUGCCCUCUAGCUUUUGCUGGAUCUGGAUUUGAAUUCCACUAUGGAGCCUCGCAUGGAGUCCUGCCUGGCGCAGGUGUUGCAGAAGGAUGUGGGGAAACGAUUGCAGGUUGGCCAAGAACUGAUAGACUAUUUCUCAGACAAACAGAAGUCUGCUGACCUUGAGCAUGACCAGACCAUGUUAGAUAAACUUGUGGAUGGACUUGCUACCUCUUGGGUGAACUCUAGCAAUUACAAGGUGGUUCUGCUGGGCAUGGACAUCCUGUCCGCCCUGGUGACCCGGCUGCAGGAUCGGUUCAAGGCGCAGAUCGGCACAGUGCUGCCAAGUCUAAUAGACAGACUAGGAGAUGCUAAAGACUCUGUGAGGGAGCAGGACCAAACUCUGCUGCUAAAGAUCAUGGAUCAAGCUGCUAAUCCCCAGUACGUAUGGGACAGAAUGCUUGGAGGCUUCAAACACAAGAAUUUCCGUACUCGAGAAGGCAUCUGUCUCUGCCUUAUAGCAACACUCAAUGCCUCUGGAGCACAGACUUUAACACUAAGCAAGAUUGUGCCACAUAUAUGCAACUUACUUGGAGAUCCAAACAGCCAGGUUCGAGAUGCAGCAAUAAACAGCUUAGUGGAAAUUUACAGACAUGUAGGAGAACGUGUGAGGGCAGAUCUCAGUAAAAAAGGAUUGCCACAGUCCCGGUUGAAUGUAAUUUUUACAAAAUUUGAUGAAGUCCAGAAAUCUGGAAACAUGAUACAAUCUGCAAAUGAUAAAAAUUUCGACGAUGAAGAUUCUGUGGAUGGUAACAGACCUUCCUCUGCUAGUUCUACAUCAUCCAAGGCUCCACCAAGUUCUCGGAGAAACGUUGGAAUGGGAACCACCCGCCGGCUUGGUUCAUCCACCCUUGGAUCCAAGUCUUCAGCUGCAAAAGAAGGAGCUGGUGCUGUUGAUGAAGAGGAUUUUAUUAAAGCAUUUGAUGAUGUACCUGUAGUACAGAUUUAUUCCAGCCGAGACCUUGAGGAAUCCAUAAACAAAAUUAGGGAAAUAUUAUCUGAUGACAAGCAUGAUUGGGAGCAGAGAGUAAAUGCUCUAAAAAAGAUUAGAUCUUUACUUUUGGCUGGUGCUGCUGAGUAUGAUAACUUCUUUCAACAUUUGCGUCUUUUGGAUGGAGCCUUUAAACUCUCUGCUAAGGACCUGCGGUCUCAGGUAGUGCGGGAGGCUUGUAUCACGUUGGGGCAUCUGUCAUCAGUUCUGGGGAAUAAGUUUGACCAUGGAGCUGAAGCCAUUAUGCCAACUAUCUUUAAUUUAAUUCCAAACAGUGCCAAAAUUAUGGCCACAUCUGGUGUUGUAGCUGUUAGGUUAAUUAUUCGGCACACACACAUCCCUAGGUUAAUACCUGUCAUAACAAGCAACUGUACCUCUAAGUCUGUCGCAGUUAGAAGGCGCUGUUUUGAAUUUUUAGAUUUGCUUUUACAAGAAUGGCAGACACAUUCACUAGAACGACACAUAUCAGUAUUAGCUGAAACAAUAAAGAAGGGAAUACAUGAUGCUGAUUCCGAAGCAAGAAUAGAAGCCAGAAAAUGUUACUGGGGUUUCCACAGUCACUUCAGCAGAGAAGCAGAGCACUUGUACCACACCUUGGAGUCCUCCUACCAGAAAGCCCUGCAGUCCCACCUGAAGAACUCAGACAGCAUAGUGUCUCUGCCUCAGUCAGACCGCUCAUCUUCCAGCUCUCAAGAGAGUCUAAAUCGUCCGCUGUCUGCCAAAAGAAGUCCUACUGGAAGUACCACAUCUAGAGCUUCUACAGUUAGUACCAAAUCUGUGUCAACGACUGGGUCCCUCCAGCGAUCUCGAAGUGAUAUUGAUGUGAACGCAGCAGCCAGUGCCAAAUCCAAAGUCUCCUCAUCUUCGGGCACGACGCCUUUCAGCUCUGCAGCAGCUUUGCCUCCAGGGUCAUACGCAUCCUUAGAGUCCAGACACAUGAGGGAAGACAUGGAGUACAUAGGCCUGGACUCAGAUGGUACUACCACUAAAGCGGAGGGUCGGAUCCGCACAAGACGGCAAAGCUCUGGGAGUGCCACCAACGUCGCCUCUACACCUGAUAACCGGGGCCGCAGUCGCGCUAAAGUGGUUUCACAGUCCCAGCGAUCCAGAUCUGCUAAUCCUGCUGGUGCUGGCAGCCGGUCAAGUUCCCCAGGAAAAUUGUUGGGAAGUGGUUAUGGUGGACUUACUGGGGGCUCCUCACGAGGCCCACCUGUGACACCGUCUUCAGAAAAGCGAAGCAAGAUUCCCAGGAGCCAGGGAUGUAGCCGGGAAACAAGUCCAAACCGAAUAGGAUUAGCACGGAGCAGCCGUAUCCCUCGACCCAGCAUGAGUCAGGGGUGCAGCCGCGAUACCAGCCGUGAGAGCAGCCGAGAUACAAGCCCUGCUCGGGGCUUUCCUCCACUUGAUCGGUUUGGGCUUGGCCAGCCAGGAAGAAUACCUGGUUCUGUGAAUGCCAUGAGAGUUCUGAGCACAAGUACAGAUCUUGAAGCUGCUGUUGCUGAUGCUUUGAAGAAGCCUGUGAGGAGGAGAUAUGAGCCGUAUGGGAUGUAUUCUGACGAUGAUGCCAACAGUGAUGCCUCAAGUGUUUGCUCUGAGCGCUCAUAUGGCUCCAGGAAUGGUGGCAUUCCCCAUUAUCUGCGGCAGACUGAGGAUGUAGCAGAAGUUCUCAACCACUGUGCUAGUUCAAACUGGUCAGAAAGGAAAGAAGGGCUUCUGGGCCUGCAGAACUUACUGAAGAGCCAAAGAACACUGAGUCGAGUUGAACUGAAAAGGUUGUGUGAGAUCUUCACUCGGAUGUUUGCUGACCCUCAUAGCAAGAGAGUUUUCAGUAUGUUUUUGGAGACUCUUGUGGAUUUUAUAAUAAUUCAUAAGGAUGAUUUACAAGACUGGCUUUUUGUUCUUCUCACACAAUUACUUAAGAAAAUGGGAGCAGAUUUACUUGGAUCUGUGCAAGCAAAAGUUCAAAAGGCUCUAGAUGUCACAAGGGACUCCUUUCCAUUUGAUCAACAAUUUAACAUUUUGAUGAGAUUUAUUGUGGAUCAAACUCAAACUCCAAACCUCAAGGUCAAAGUUGCAAUCCUGAAAUACAUUGAGUCUCUGGCCAGACAGAUGGAUCCAACAGAUUUUGUAAACUCUAGUGAGACAAGGCUUGCUGUUUCUAGAAUCAUAACCUGGACAACAGAACCAAAGAGUUCAGACGUGAGAAAGGCAGCACAGAUUGUGCUAAUCUCUCUGUUUGAAUUGAAUACUCCUGAAUUUACCAUGUUACUUGGUGCCUUGCCAAAAACAUUCCAGGAUGGUGCCACCAAACUCCUGCACAACCACCUCAAGAAUUCCAGUAACACCAGUGUGGGCUCUCCAAGCAAUACGAUUGGCCGGACGCCCUCCCGACACACCAGCAGCAGGACCAGCCCCCUGACCUCACCCACCAACUGUUCCCAUGGGGGUCUGUCUCCAAGUCGGUUAUGGGGUUGGAGUGCCGACGGGUUAGCGAAGCACCCACCUCCCUUUUCUCAGCCUAACUCCAUCCCCACCGCUCCCUCCCACAAGGCUCUCAGGCGCUCUUACUCUCCCAGGUAACAAGCUACCUGUCAAACUUGUCUGAGGUGUCACAAUAUUAUUGCAUUUCCAAGGUCGUCUCAGGUCUUUGGGAAAGCCUCUAAGCUGCCUCCAGUGUGGUCCCUUCCUUGGUGUCACAUAGCAGGAGUAGAGCCUUGGUGAGAAGUGUGAGCAGGUGUGUGAUCUUUGCCAAAUCUCACAAGUAUGGUUCCUGCUGUGUCACAGGGACAGAUGACCCUUUAUAAGCUGAUCAGAUUCAUCACCACCUAUUAUUGUGGGCCUUUCUGUACAGUGCAGUGCUCAGCCCCCAGAAAGACCUCAGGAAAUGCUGUGAGGUCAGCGUGGGCAAUAGUGGGAGCAGUUUCCUUAGCAUGCGUCUAAAGUGCAGAAGACAUUCCCCUGAGAAGCCAAAAAGACCUCUUUCCCAAACCAUACCUGUCACUCUCAGCCUUGCUAUUGACUAUUUGUAACUGAUUUCUUUCCUAACAUACUGUCAUAUGAGGGUAGUCUGAGCACACAGAUCCAGAAAGGAGUCCCCAAGAGGCAGGAUAACUGUUACAGCUCACUAAGGAUGCCCUGCCUCUAAGAAGGAGAAACGUCAGUCCCUUCACGCACCCCCACAGUUGAUGCUGAAUGCGGCAUCAUGGACACUGGUUAUGCAACAAUGUUAUGAGUCUGGAAGAAGGGGUGGGCUUCCCUCAGAUGCUGAAUCUGUGGUACAAAGAAGGGUCCACAUAGUACUGCAGAUGUCUAUUUCAGGGUCUCUUGGGGAUGCUUUUUAUAAGGUCCAAAGAUCAGAGAAUCUCUUCCCUAGAAACCUGUUAGAGCACUGGGCAGUCCAGCUGUCACUGUUCUUUGUGAGAUGAGUUUCUAUCCUCUAUAAUAGAGGGUGUGAUAGGAAAAGGGUUAAAAAAAAAAAAGACCUGUUACUUUUGAAAUACUUCAUAGAUAGCUUUUGUGCAGAUUUGCAUUCUGACUUUUGUGGAAUACAAAUAAUCUACAUAGUGAAGCCAAAAACAGUAAAUGAAAUAUUUUAACAACACCUUCCUUUUGAAGCUCUUAUACCUCUAAAAGUCAUUUCUAAAAUGUACAGAGAACCCUGCGAUGAAUGUUUCUAGAUACACAAGGUUAGGGCAAGCAGGCGAGGAGACGGCUGCUGUCUUUAAUGUUAACAAAGCAGGUCACUCCUUUUUCUUUUUUUUAAGGUUAGCUGUGCCUCCAAGUGUAAGAUCAGUUGGUUGACUAUCUCCCAGUAUGUUGACCUGUAUUCCCUCAUGGGCACUCAGCUUCACCACCAGCCAGCCAUCAAGAUUGCCCCUCCAGAGCACAUCCCAUUCCUAGGAUCAUCUUUCACAUACAUACACGAUACAUAUUGACCUAACUCAUUAAGAGAGAAUGCUUACUGAAUACUUAUAACUUCUGUUGCCCAUUGGAGGCAGGGAUAGUUGACUAGAGACUUUUACAUUUAGAAAACCUAUCAGUUACAUAAAACUAAGAGGGAAUCUGUAUGUCUGUCUAUUUGUUCUGUGCCAAAAUCCUAUUGAUUCCAUAACAAAGAAUGACUAUCCUUAUUCUAUACAUUGUACCCUUUUCCUACAAAAUGACGAAGAAGGCAGGCUUCUCUCUCCAGUUUCUCUCUCUUGGAGACCUGACCCCAUGUUCUCCUCCCUCCCCACGACAUGGAUCCUUUAGCGGGCAAGCCCAGGGCUGCUUUCAGCUUCCAUGUUGGGUGGCAUGGCCUAACCUUAGGUCAGUGACUAUUGGCUGAUUAAGGAAUUCUCCCUAAUCUAAAAAACCCUAAGAGAGCCCUUCUGGAGUCUAACCAGAGUAUUUACAGGUGAUCAGGGCCUGACCUCUAACCCAAGGAUUAUGUCCUGGGGUUGUCUCAGGGCUGAAACAAGACAGGCUGUGGGGCAGAUGGCAGAUUGAGGUUUCCCCAGGUCUCUUCUCAGUCAGCUUCUGAGGCCGUCCUGCUGCUCCCUCAUAUACUGCUUGUGAGGACACAAUAUCUACCCUCCCUGAUGAUGGCUUCCAUGGGAAGUUCCUUUUUCCUUUAAGUGAGAACUUAACAGAUACUGAUUUGGAAAAAUAUAAUUCAAGCCAAAGCAUAAAAAUAGCAAAGAAAGUAGCAUGGUCUGUUUCCUCCUAGAGGUAAGCAGUUAUGCCUCUCACCUGCAGCUCACAGUUAUAGCUUCAUACCAAGGAGAUACUUCAAACCCCAGGCUAGUGAGUCUAAAAGAAGACACCUUCAAUUGUUCUUGGUUCUGCAAAUGGUGCUCCUGAAUUGGGAGUUUGAGUUGGUUUAUUAAUUGAAAGUGAGAAGGAGGAAAUUACCUGGCAGAAUCCUUUAUUUUCUUAUUUUAAAAAGAGGCUAUUGUAAUAGUGAAGUGAUGUGAUCUGAAAUGAAAUAUUUUUAAGAAAGUUCAGGUUAAGAAUAAUGAGAUGAAUUAUCUGAAAGCUGACAUUAUCUGAAGCGACAUAUGGAAAAUAAUAUUGUGACAUCCCUUAAAAAAACUUGAACGUUCCCCCAGACUUCCUCUUGUCCAUCCCAUCAUUCUUUCAGUUUUUUGGAUUUUUUUUCUUUUGCAUGGGCUAUGCUGUUAUUUUUGGUUGUUGUGAUUAAAAGUAUUUUAAGGCAUUUUUUUACAUCUUGUAUAUAUAUUUUUUGUUUGAGUCAUAAUACUCAGUCUUUAUAUAUAAAAAAUAGUGUACUGGCCAGAUGUAUAAAUGCCUUGUCCAUACAAAAGCUAGUAUUGUGGUGUCCUCAGAAGGAGCGGGGGAGCCUCUGGCCCCUUGGUCAUGCCUUUCUCACAUCUAAGGAGUGUUGCCUCUUUGACAGACAGCCUUGUGAACAUAGAAGAGGUUGAAAUCUUAAAUUCUCUUCAGGUUUUUUAUUCUACCUCCUGUCAGUUUAGACAUGGAAUUUCAACAGCAAACCUGUUCAAGGUUCACAUUUCUUUUUGUUUGAUGCUCAAGUCAAUCUUUGAGUUGAAUUUUUUUUUUUUUUUUGUGAACUCUCCAAAUAUUCAUUCAUCAGGAAAGGUGGGUUUUAUCUGGGCCAUAUUUGCAAUUCUAGACAAAUAGCUCCCAUCUUUGAGAUUGUGGUCAGCUCUUGGGCUCUAGAACCUACCAGCACCAGCCCUAGAAAACACUUGGAUCAUUGCUACAUCAAGCCAGUAGAGAUCUGGCCACUCCAAGUGAGAGCUCUCCAAAUCUUACCUUGCUCAUCUGCCCCAACUUUUUUUUUUUUUUUUUUUAAGGCAGAAUACUUAAGGAAGAGUAUUUACUAAAUGUUCAUCAUUUUUACAUUACAGGAAACUCACUUUGGGAAUGUACAGGAUUGGUUGUGUUGCCCUUAGGAAGGAUACUUCGUUUCUUCAGUUACUACUCUUUUGAAGAACAGGAAGAUUGCUUUUCUUUAGUCCUUAAACAGUGUUGCAUGCUUACAGCCAAGGAUUCUUCGCGUGUCCCUAGCAAUCCUCAGUAUAGCUCAGGACUAUUUUAAAAAUUAAAUUAGACGAAUUCAUCUGAUCUUUUCUUGAAACUUUCUUGAAACAAGUGACAUUUAAACUAAGAUUUUUUUUUAACUUGCCCUUGGUUGACUGUUGCUUCGUGUUUUGCUUGCUUUAUGCUGAUAUAUCCAUCCCAUGCUUUUCUUUUAUAUUCUCAGGAUGGUUUUUGUUCUCAGGAUUCUCCCUGUUUCAGUGCACUUUCCAGACAUCUAAAAGGCACUUGUUGACAAACUGCAGUGCACCAAAAAGGAUUGUUUGGCUUUUUUGCUUCAUUUCAUGUUUUGCUGUGCCCAAUGUCUAUAAAGACAGCAGUCAAUAACACUUUUCUGUGAACAACAAAUAUUUCUUGCUUUUAUGAGGAUUUUUAGAUGUCCAUCCAGGAAUGUGACUUUUUAUAAAAUCUGCUUUGAUUAUAAAACUCCAAACAGAAGCAUGUAGAAGAGUCUGAUAUUAAUAGCAAGCUCAUGGGUGAGAUGAUGUGAGAGUUACUUUCUGGGCCUGUUCAUAGGGUGGAUCUGACUUUGAGUCUAGGGUUUUUUGUUUUGUUUUGUUUUAAUAGGGUUUUAUUUGUUUUCUGGAUUGGAUACCUGGGAGUAUAACCUAGCCUUGUGAGGUCAUUUACUUUGCUCCUUUGAAAUUUGCUUAUAGUACUAGCUUUAUUUCCAACUGCCCAUUCCUCUUAAGUUUGUACAUUUGAGACCAGUAACAACCAAACUCCUUUUUUCCAUCUUCAAAAUAAGAAAGUUAUUUUUCCACUUUCAUUAUCUCGUGCCUUCAGUCACCAGUGUCACUCUUUGAGUUCCUGCAUUCUCGUGGUUACUGUUGUUUCCCACUGGUUUUUAUUGAGUGCUGAUGUAAUGUGUUUGGCAGAUUUAACAAAGAAGAUGUGUAAUUGUCCGGUGGUGGUACUCUAACAAAAGACGUCUCCUUUUCAUUCCAAAUCACCCAAUAAACAAAACUAUAAAUAUGUCUUAUUCUUUAAAUUGUGGGAAGUAACUUAUGCCCAUAUCUCAGUUCUAUGUAUAUGCCUCGAUUUAAGAAAUAAAAUAUUUUUUAUCUUUAG